AGAGCACUCAUCAGCAUGCUUCCUCCUUCUCUCUAACUGUGUCCUUUAGAUCCAGGAGGGAUAUUUGCUACCACCACCAGCUAAUGCUGAUUUGCUACCAGCACAAGGCCCAGGUCCUUGUCUGGUCUGUACCCCAUUACAAGGUUCUCCAGGAACAGACAUCACCACCUCUGCCUAGAUCCUGAAAUUUCACAAAUGUAGGUUCUUUCUUACCCGUUCUUUUUAUUCCUCUAUUUACAAGCACAAUGACACCCACCCCUCAUCUUCUUCCUGAAAUACCUGGCUCUGAUCUCAGGCAUCCAUUCCAGAAAUCAACACAGCUAUGCAAUUGCAUCUUUUAUUAAAUACUCCCAACUCCAUUUCAAAUCCAGAGAAUCCAGAGCAGGAGCAAGAGACCAACCUAUCAUCUGGAAACUCAAGGUGUAAACAUUAGUGCCAAAGAUUAGUCAUGAAGGCCAACUACAGCGCAGAGGAGCGCUUUCUCCUGCUGGGUUUCUCCGACUGGCCUUCCCUGCAGCCGGUCCUCUUCGCCCUUGUCCUCCUGUGCUACCUCCUGACCUUGACGGGCAACUCGGCGCUGGUGCUGCUGGCGGUGCGCGACCCGCGCCUGCACACGCCCAUGUACUACUUCCUCUGCCACCUGGCCUUGGUAGACGCGGGCUUCACUACUAGCGUGGUGCCGCCGCUGCUGGCCAACCUGCGCGGACCAGCGCUCUGGCUGCCGCGCAGCCACUGCACGGCCCAGCUGUGCGCAUCGCUGGCUCUGGGUUCCGCCGAAUGCGUCCUCCUGGCGGUGAUGGCUCUGGACCGCGCGGCCGCAGUGUGCCGCCCGCUGCGCUAUGCGGGGCUCGUCUCCCCGCGCCUAUGUCGCACGCUGGCCAGCGCCUCCUGGCUAAGUGGCCUCACCAACUCGGUUGCGCAAACCGCGCUCCUGGCUGAGCGGCCGCUGUGCGCGCCCCGCCUGCUGGACCACUUCAUCUGUGAGCUGCCGGCGUUGCUCAAGCUGGCCUGCGGAGGCGACGGAGACACUACCGAGAACCAGAUGUUCGCCGCCCGCGUGGUCAUCCUGCUGCUGCCGUUUGCCGUCAUCCUGGCCUCCUACGGUGCCGUGGCCCGAGCUGUCUGUUGCAUGCGGUUCAGCGGAGGCCGGAGGAGGGCGGUGGGCACGUGUGGGUCCCACCUGACAGCCGUCUGCCUGUUCUACGGCUCGGCCAUCUACACCUACCUGCAGCCCGCGCAGCGCUACAACCAGGCACGGGGCAAGUUCGUAUCGCUCUUCUACACCGUGGUCACACCUGCUCUCAACCCGCUCAUCUACACCCUCAGGAAUAAGAAAGUGAAGGGGGCAGCGAGGAGGCUGCUGCGGAGUCUGGGGAGAGGCCAGGCUGGGCAGUGAGUAGUUGGGGAGGGGAGAAAGUAUUAAGCCAGAACCCAAGGAUGGAAAUACCCCUUAGUGAGUCAGUUUAGACUUCAGGCUGUUCAUUUUUGUAUGAUAAUCUGCAAGAUUUGUCCUAAGGAGUCCAAUGGGGGAUAUGUUUUCCUCCCGUGAGGAAAUGUUUAGUUCUUGAGGGAAAAUCCCUAAAUCCUCUAUAUACUCAGGUUUAGGGAAGGAAAACCUACCCCUCACAACUCCACGCGCAGGGAAAAUGAUGGACGUGAUGCUCGCCUUUAGCUUCCUCCCUAUCUGAUGGAAGACCAUGGAAGACCUCUUGGUCUCUGCAAUCAGAAGUCUCAAGUUGACAAGAAAAUCAUAGUCCCUACCCUGCAGGAGAGGGUACAUCCAGAAAAAGCGACCAUGGACUCUAUUCUCAGAAAUCAGUCCAACUUAGUGCAGACCUGGCCAGAUGACCAGUGCCCUCCCCGGGGCAUUUCACCCAUAAAUGUGAUGAGGAAAGCCCAUAAAUGGUGGUGAAUUUUGCUGAGUGGGGUUAAGACUGGAAACCCCCCUGCAGGAGUUGGUUCUUGAGCAAGUUUUAAAGAAACAAGGAACUAGGAUGAGUGUGGAAGAAGGCGGGCACGUCUCAGCCCGUGAAAAAAACUCACAGGUGAUCAGUAGUGAGUCAUGAGAGAGAGAGCAAGAGAGAGAGUCAGAGAGAGGAGUAAAUGGAGGGAGGAAGAUGGAGGAAGGGACUCAAGUUCUCAAGACAGGAACAGGGAUCUCCUCAUGAAAAAAAGAAGAGAGGAAAAUGCUCAAUCAGCAGAACCUGAGCAGAAUAUUGAGGUCAACCCAGAAGCCAGCUCCUCACCCACCCUCACCCAGACUGGCGCCCUCAUCCUGGAGAAGACCUGCUAGACCCUAAGGCAGGUAGGAGAGAGGGUGGUCCACAGUCCCCCAGCUUUAGAAAGUUUGUUCGCUCCCAAUGUCCAUCUACCCCUAGGAAUCCCCACUAGUUAAACAGAAUUGCUAGAUCCCUGUGGAAAAUACCUUUCCUUGCCCACCAUCAUCCCCAGAAAUAAUAACUAUUUUAGUUGGGUGUGAGACAUAGAGAAUAAAAGGGGGCAUGGUGCCAGACUUCAUUUCAUACAAAUAGCUUUAAAGGAGAAGAGGGGGGAAGGAGUUUAAUUUAGUUUCUAAAAUGUUUAGUAAUUUGAUUGUGAUCAUGUCAGAGCAACUAAUUCAUUUUAUAAAAUAUCAUUUCACUAUGCUCUAUAAGUAGAAAUUCAAUUUGGUUCAACCAUUAUUGAGUGAUAUAAAUAAAGCACUGGACUUAACAAAGACAGAAAUACAGAAAUCAGUAGAACAUGGAUCCCAACCUAAAACUUACUCUCUUGUCAUAAAGGAAAGGAGAUAGGAGUUUUUGCAUAAAUAACAAGGUAUCAAGACAGAAUUAAAUUCCAAGCUGGCUUUGAAUGCUCUAUUUUGCCUUAAAAAUUUAUUUACUAGUCUCAGUAAUACAUUAGUAAAAAUCAUGUCACUUAAUUAAUUGUGUUAGAAUCAAAGAAACAUAGAGUUGGGCAAUAUACUUCAUCCUACCCAUCCCACCCAAAUCUUACUCUACUCAUCUCAUUCUCAUUAAUUUUGGGAAAUCAUCAGAAGAUGUGUUCGUUGAGUAAGAGAUUAAAAGAAAUAAGCUUUUUGACCCCUGCCAACACCCCAUGCCCAGGGUGGUCACCCUCCAAUACAAUAAGAUGCCAGGAAGAGUAAGUUGCCCUUUCUGAUGCCGUAAUCUGCCAUCAUCUUCCCAUCUUCCAGUCUCUUUCCAUUGCAAGUCACAAUCUGGGUCUCAGGGAUUAUACCCGUCUUAGUCUCGAUCAUUGCUUUCACUUGUGCCACUGAGCUGGACCUUCGCACCUGGAGGAGGUGCCUCUUUGCCUCAUCACCUGACUCCACAAGAAACAAGGGCAGCUCCUCAUCACUGGGCUUCACCACUUUCAGGGUAAGGUGGAUGGUCUUCUCUUUGUCAAUGCCGUAAGAUGAGAGGCUUCUCCGUGGCUUUAAGAUCUUGGAGCCCAGCAAAAGAACCUGGUCCUGCACAGGAACCUUGGUCUUAGACCGGACAUGUUCUUUGAUUUUUUUCACGCUGUCAUAUGGGUUGGCAUCAAAGGUCAUUAAAUCCCAUUCCUCGGAACGGACAUGCACCUGGGAAGUGAAAGCCACAAGACAGUUACCUAGGAUGCCUGCCUCCUUUACACUUCUACUCCCCACCACAAUGGCUCCCCCUCUUCCACUAUCUAUCUGGUCCUCUAGCUCCUAUUCAGUAGCCAGUGUCCCUCUCUUUCUUGGAACUUCUUUUUUGGAAUUACCAAGUUACAACACAAAUAAGAUAAUUUGUCCCAUUCCUUUAUAAUCACACCUUUUUUUCGAUCUUGAGAAUGGAAAAUAAAAUCCUGAGCCCCCAACCAACUGAACGGACGCUCUUUUGCUCAGGGGGACCCUAGAGAAACUUUAAAAACUUAGUCAUUGGGCCAAGGGUGGUGGCUUACACCUGUAAUCCCAGAACUUUGGGAAGCUGAGGCAGGCUGAUCAAUUGAUGCUGGGAGUUCGAGACCAGCCUGGUGAACUUGGUGAAACUCUGUCUCUACUAAAAAUACAAAAAUUAGCCAGUAGUGGUGGCAAGUCCCUGUAAUCCCAGCUACUCAGGAGGCUGAGGCAGGAGAAUCAUUUGAAUCCAGGAGGCAGAGGUUGCAGUGAGUGGAGAUGGCACUACUGCACUCCAGCCAGGGCAACAGAGUGAGACUCUGUCUCAAAAAUAUAAAUAAAUAAAACAUUCAGUCAUGAUGGAACAGGAGGUUGGAUAUGCCUCAUUGUAUCUUCUCCCUUUUGCAGUUUAGACACAACUGACCAGCAAAGUUAGAGAUUAUAAGACUGAGAGAAUGGAUUCUUUGUGGCAAUAAGAUAGCAAAUUAUAAACAAGACCGAGGGCUAUAACAGGCAAAAGUUAAGUCAUGCAUCCCUUACACUUAAAGAAUAAACUAUGUUCUGCCACAAAGUUUUUUCUUUUUUCUCUAGCAGCUAAACAAGCACUGGCCUUGACAGGAACAAUAUUAAAACAAUUACAGCUCACCCUGUGUUGGGGAACACAGGCUAACUGACCCCGUGUUCCACAAGCCAUAACUACAGUUUUAAUUGGACAAAAGACUGAUUUCAGUAAUUUUCUCCUGAUAAGAGACCACUGACCAUGGACUGGUUCUGGCUAGUUUACAGAAGCUGUGCAUUUGAAUGCCUUUGUGUCCCUGCUUCACCUUUUCAUGUAUAAGGCCUAACUGUAAUGCAAUUAAAUGUUAAGUCUCCACUUCAGAGUGACCAUGGGUGGUAUGUAACAUGCAAGCUUAUUCAAUAUGCAUGCAUUAGGACCCCCUCCAUGAAUAUUCAUUGCCUCUGCUAUAACCUAUUGGAUAUGUAUACUUAGCAAACCCCUUCAGCAUAAAUUCCUGUGUCACCUUUCCUCCUGCAAAGUGCUUGCUUUUGGUUUUCAAUCAGAAGCAAAACUUCCCAGCCUGUCAGAAUGGCUACCUUGCAGACUAUAACCUUUCAUAAGAAAUAAACUCCCCUUCUAAAUUUA